CCCUUCCGGUGGAGCCAGCGCUGCGACCGCCUGCAGAAGGUUGACUGCGUGGUAGGGGGCCCAGAGCAAGCCGAAGGCAAGCACGAUGGCGCUCACCAGCCGGCCCACCCGCGCCCCGUGCCGCCCGGAGCCCCAGCGGGCGCCCCGCAGCCGUGCCAGCGUCACGCUGUAGCAGCCGAGCAUCAGCCCGAAAGGAAGCACGAAAGCGGUCAGAGUCUCCAGGCUCAGGUGGGCGGCGGCGUGGACCGGCGACGGGUGGCACAGCUGGCAUACGCGGUCCCUCCACAGGUGGCGGUAGACGGCGGCCGGGACGGCGAGCAACAGGGCGGCCAGCCAGACCGCCAGCAGCAGGCGGCGGGCCAGGGCCGGGCUGCGCAGCCGAGGCGCCAGGAAGGGGCGGGUGACUGCGAGGCAGCGCUGCAGGCUGAGCAGGCCGGUGAGCAGCACGCUGGCGUACAUGCUGAGCGCGCACACGUAGUACACCGCCUUGCAGCCCGCCUGGCCCAGCGGCCAGGCCUGCCGGGUCAGGAAGGCCACAAAGAGCGGCGUGAGCAGCAGCACCGCGCCGUCGGCCAGCGCCAGGUGCAGCACAAGCGUGGCCGCCAGCGGUCGCCCCCGUGCAGGCCGCCAGCCCGCCAAGCUCCACACCACGAAGCCGUUGCCAGGCAGCCCCAGCAGCGCCGCCAGCAGCAGGAAGGCUGUGCCUGUGGCCCGCGAAGUCUUCCAGCUCAGCAGUGUCUCGUUCCCUGGGGGACGGUAGCAGACCGACAUCCUUCUGGGCCUACAGCCUGCCUCUUUUCUGCCUGGGAGUCCUGACUUCCACGAGGACCCAGACCCCACCUCAAACACAACUCCUUCUUGGAACCCAGAUCCCCUGCUCCCAGUCAGUUGACCUGCCCCACUCCUGGCCUCCUUCCCAGAGCUCAGUGGUAAACAGGCAUAAAGUCAUCACCCCAGGCUGUCACUAUCUCUACCACCACUCCUCUAGUCUGGCCCCUCCUUCUUUGUCCAGCCCCAUUCUAGCACAUCUGGGCAAAACUGGAUGGUGGGGUGUAAAGGGACGUGCACAGAUCUACUUACCAAGCUGGGAGCAAGCAGGAUUGGGGGCCUGGAGAAGCUGAAAGGUUAAGCAGCAGUAGGCGAGGUGCCUACUCCUGUCCUGUGCCUAUCACAUUUGCAGAGGGUAAGACAAGAAUGGGGAGGGACAAGAUGAGGCUCAUCCUGGGCCUCUCCUGGGGCCCCUCCCUCACCCUGCUCCUUCCCAUCACCAACGCACCCAGGCGUCCAGGCAUGUGAGAGCCUGCCUUGCCAGGAAACAGCACAAGCUGAAGUGGGGCAGUAAGAUUCCCUGGUGGUGGAAGGAAAUAGGAGGACUCUGCUGAAUCCUGGUCCUGCUUCUGUUCUCAUCCCUCCCCCAGCUCUGGCCCCAAUCCUCCCAGCCCACCUUCUGCAGUGUGUAUGUUGCCUGGUCUCUCUGGCCUGCAGAGGUGACCCAAACAACUCAGUCCCCCACCUGCCUUAUCCUUGCCUGUUUCCAGUCUCCUGGUCCGGCUGAGCCCCUGGCCUCCUACCUCCUCCCACCUCUUGCCUCAGGCCCUGCCCCAGUCACUCCACCCUCAGGGCUCUCACCGGGCUGUCAAUGACAGCUUUUCCAUGUAAGGCAUGGUGCUAGGUUCCAGGAGGAACAGGGGAUGCAUGGAGGCAUAAUGGUUAGGGAGUCAUGACACACAACCAUGAAGAGGCCCCAUUACCAGGCUGCACCAGGAUACAAGACAAGAAAGGAAAGGAUGAGUAGGGACAUACUAAGAAGCAGCCCUCUCCUCUUGGAAAAGUCAAGCAAAACUUGGAAAUGAAGAGAUUUGAGGGGGGCCUGGCAGAUGGAUAGAGCUGGGGGAAGGGAAAAGAAAGGCCUCUGCUCAAGUAACAGCCAGAACUUGAGGUUGCUUGGGGAGGGCACCAGGAGCACUGUCUUAGUUUGGGUUCUUCCAAAGCAGAGCUUGAGCUAAGGGCUUGGGUACAGGUGAUCCUGUAUUCUUGAGCUAAGGGCUUGGGUACAGGUGAUCCUGUAUUUGGGAGGUUAACUCAGGAAGUGAGGGCAUAAGGUAAAACAAGAGAGAGGAAAGCCAUUAAGAGUAUGUUAAGUCCCUUCAGUAGGCCUUGGGAACCUCUGAGAAAAGUAUAGAUUGCCCAAGACAAAAGACUGGCAGGGUGAUCAGUCCAAAGCAUUUAUUAGGAGAAUGUACUUAAUGAGUGGGCUACAGCGUAUCCUCACAACAGACAGUGAGAGAGAGUUGUUCUACCUGGGUAUAUCCAAAACAAGGGGGUCAGGGUAUGGAGUUUACGAGGGUUCAAGGUAUUUGGUUCAGGGCCAGGGCCAGUUUUUUUCAGUGUUUUGGGCAACAACCUGAAUACCUUUUCAAGGCUCUGGCUUGGGCUCAAGCCUGCAGGGGAAAUGCAACUGGCCAGGUCACAGGGCAAUCAAGUUACUCUGUGUUUCUUUGUCAGGACACAGAAAAAAAGUGGGGAAGCUGGGGGACCCUACAAGGAUCCUUGGCAGGAAAGCAGGGAUUGUGUUCAUUUGAGGGUUUCACUGUCAGUGAGAGUCUCAGCUUCCAUGCAACUGUCCAUCACGGCUGCAACUGAAAUCAGAGCUGGGACACAGCGCACCAGAAGCUAAAGUCUUGAUGCCAUCAAAGGACAUCCCUGCCCCAUUCACAUCUCUGUCACGUCCACUAAUCGGCAAAAGGAGAAAAGUGAGAGAAGAUGACCUAAGUGUGACUGCAGCAGGCAGCUCUGGAAAAUGAAGCCAGAGCAGUGAGCCAGCCCCUCCUCCGACCAAGGAGGAAGGAAAGAGCAGGUAAGCAGGAAGGCCAGUGUCCCAGACAGGACCCUAAUGAUCCUGAAUCCAUGUAUCAGGAUCCAUCCUCUCCUUACACCCUUCCUGGACACAGUCUCACCUCUCAUUUUCCAAAGCCCUGCCAUGCUGCCAUCCCACUUCCCCACACUCUGCCCCGGGUUCCCUUUUCCUAAAGCUGCAGCUUAUGGCUUCUCCAGUAGGUGGCAGCACACACAGAGCCACUCAUAAACUGCAGCUUCUCAGAGCCUGAGAGCCAGAAACCGUCCCCAGAAAUUCCCUCCAUAGAAAUAAAAAAACACCAGAAGUCACAUUUCAUCCUUUUACAUGGUUCCCAUCUACCCUCACAACACAUGUCAUCACCAAAGACACACAUACAAGCUCCAAUGGCUUUUGCCAGGCAAUUCUUCCUCCAGGACCCCAUCUGGCCCCUCCCUCAUCCCUCCCCUUGGACUUUGCCCUUCUUACUGGCCAGGCAGGGGGGCCAGAGUCCAGGCUUGACUCAUUCCCACCUUGUCCUGGGCUGAGAUCCCAGGUUUGUAACAGAAAACACCACUAAAGCCCCAGCACAGGAGAGAACCACCCAGCCCAGAAGUUCCAGGGAAGGAACUCUCCGGUCCACCAUGGAGUACCUCUCAGCUCUGAACCCCAGUGACUUACUCAGGUCAGUAUCUAAUAUAAGCUCGGAGUUUGGACGGAGGGUCUGGACCUCAGCUCCACCACCCCAGCGACCUUUCCGUGUCUGUGAUCACAAGCGGACCAUCCGGAAAGGCCUGACAGCUGCCACCCGCCAGGAGCUGCUAGCCAAAGCAUUGGAGACCCUACUGCUGAAUGGAGUGCUAACCCUGGUGCUAGAGGAGGAUGGAACUGCAGUGGACAGUGAGGACUUCUUCCAGCUGCUGGAGGAUGACACGUGCCUGAUGGUGUUGCAGUCUGGUCAGAGCUGGAGCCCUACAAGGAGUGGAGUGCUGUCAUAUGGCCUGGGACGGGAGAGGCCCAAGCACAGCAAGGACAUCGCCCGAUUCACCUUUGACGUGUACAAGCAAAACCCUCGAGACCUCUUUGGCAGCCUGAAUGUCAAAGCCACAUUCUACGGGCUCUACUCUAUGAGUUGUGACUUUCAAGGACUUGGCCCAAAGAAAGUACUCAGGGAGCUCCUUCGUUGGACCUCCACACUGCUGCAAGGCCUGGGCCAUAUGUUGCUGGGAAUUUCCUCCACCCUUCGUCAUGCAGUGGAGGGGGCUGAGCAGUGGCAGCAGAAGGGCCGCCUCCAUUCCUACUAAGGGGCUCUGAGCUUCUGCCCCCAGAAUCAUUCCAACCGACCCACUGCAAAGACUAUGACAGCAUCAAAUUUCAGGACCUGCAGACAGUACAGGCUAGAUAACCCACCCAAUUUCCCCACUGUCCUCUGAUCCCCUCGUGACAGAACCUUUCAGCAUAACGCCUCACAUCCCAAGUCUAUACCCUUACCUGAAGAAUGCUGUUCUUUCCUAGCCACCUUUCUGGCCUCCCACUUGCCCUGAAAGGCCAAGAUCAAGAUGUCCCCCAGGCAUCUUGAUCCCAGCCUGACUGCUGCUACAUCUAAUCCCCUACCAAUGCCUCCUGUCCCUAAACUCCCCAGCAUACUGAUGACAGCCCUCUCUGACUUUACCUUGAGAUCUGUCUUCAUACCCUUCCCCUCAAACUAACAAAAACAUUUCCAAUAAAAAUAUCAAAUAUUUACCACUAA